GUGCACAAUUGUGAGGGCUUAACUGGGUUUCCAGGAAGUACGUAAUUCACACUCUAAAUGUGACAAGCAUGACUGCCCAUAAACCUAACGACUUUUUUAAGAGACCAAAAUUCAGAAUGUUAUUCUCUCUGAAACUGCACUUAGUAACCCAGCAGAAAACUGUUCAGAGAUCUGCUCCCAUUGCAAUGAAGGCAUCUGGACAUACCAGUGGUGAUGGGCAGAAUCUGUUUACGAAAGACGUGACAGUGAUCGAGGGAGAGGUUGCGACCAUCAGUUGCCAAGUCAAUAAGAGUGACGACUCUGUGAUUCAGCUACUGAAUCCCAACAGGCAGACCAUUUAUUUCAGGGACUUCAGGCCUUUGAAGGACAGCAGGUUUCAGUUGCUGAAUUUUUCUAGCAGUGAACUCAAAGUAUCAUUGACAAACGUCUCAAUUUCUGAUGAAGGAAGAUACUUUUGCCAGCUCUAUACCGAUCCCCCACAGGAAAGUUACACCACCAUCACAGUCCUGGUCCCACCACGUAAUCUGAUGAUCGAUAUCCAGAAAGACACUGCGGUGGAAGGUGAGGAGAUUGAAGUCAACUGCACUGCUAUGGCCAGCAAGCCAGCCACGACUAUCAGGUGGUUCAAAGGGAACACAGAGCUAAAAGGCAAAUCGGAGGUGGAAGAGUGGUCAGACAUGUACACUGUGACCAGUCAGCUGAUGCUGAAGGUGCACAAGGAGGACGAUGGGGUCCCAGUGAUCUGCCAGGUGGAGCACCCUGCGGUCACUGGAAACCUGCAGACCCAGCGGUAUCUAGAAGUACAGUAUAAGCCUCAAGUGCACAUUCAGAUGACUUAUCCUCUACAAGGCUUAACCCGGGAAGGGGACGCGCUUGAGUUAACAUGUGAAGCCAUCGGGAAGCCCCAGCCUGUGAUGGUAACUUGGGUGAGAGUCGAUGAUGAAAUGCCUCAACACGCCGUACUGUCUGGGCCCAACCUGUUCAUCAAUAACCUAAACAAAACAGAUAAUGGUACAUACCGCUGUGAAGCUUCAAACAUAGUGGGGAAAGCUCACUCGGAUUAUAUGCUGUAUGUAUACGAUCCCCCCACAACUAUCCCUCCUCCCACAACAACCACCACCACCACCACCACCACCACCACCACCAUCCUUACCAUCAUCACAGACACAACGGCGACGACAGAACCAGCAGUUCACGGCCUUACUCAGUUGCCCAAUUCCGCAGAAGAACUGGACAGUGAGGACCUCUCAGAUUCCCGAGCAGGUGAAGAAGGCUCGAUCAGGGCAGUGGAUCAUGCCGUGAUCGGUGGCGUCGUGGCGGUGGUGGUGUUCGCCAUGCUGUGCUUGCUCAUCAUUCUGGGGCGCUAUUUUGCCAGACAUAAAGGUACAUACUUCACUCAUGAAGCCAAAGGAGCCGAUGACGCAGCAGACGCAGACACAGCUAUAAUCAAUGCAGAAGGAGGACAGAACAACUCCGAAGAAAAGAAAGAGUACUUCAUCUAGAUCAGCCUUUUUGUUUCAAUGAGGUGUCCAACUGGCCCUAUUUAGAUGAUAAAGAGACAGUGAUAUUGGAACUUGCGAGAAAUUCGUGUGUUUUUUUAUGAAUGGGUGGAAAGGUGUGAGACUGGGAAGGCUUGGGAUUUGCUGUGUAAAAAAAAAAAAAAUGUUCUUUGGAAAGUACACUCUGCUGUUUGACACCUCUUUUUUCGUUUGUUUGUUUGUUUAAUUUUUAUUUCUUCCUACCAAGUCAAACUUGGAUACUUGGAUUUAGUUUCAGUAGAUUGCAGAAAAUUCUGUGCCUUGUUUUUUGUUUGUUUGUUGCGUUCCUUUCUUUUCCCCCUUUGUGCACAUUUAUUUCCUCCCUCUACCCCAAUUUCGGAUUUUUUCCAAAAUCUCCCAUUUUGGAAUUUGCCUGCUGGGAUUCCUUAGACUCUUUUCCUUCCCUUUUCUGUUCUAGUUUUUUACUUUUGUUUAUUUUUAUGGUAACUGCUUUCUGUUCCAAAUUCAGUUUCAUAAAAGGAGAACCAGCACAGCUUAGAUUUCAUAGUUCAGAAUUUAGUGUAUCCAUAAUGCAUUCUUCUCUGUUGUCGUAAAGAUUUGGGUGAACAAACAAUGAAAACUCUUUGCUGCUGCCCAUGUUUCAAAUACUUAGAGCAGUGAAGACUAGAAAAUUAGACUGUGAUUCAGAAAAUGUUCUGUUUGCUGUGGAACUACAUUACUGUACAGGGUUAUCUGCAAGUGAGGUGUGUCACAAUGAGAUUGAAUUUCACUGUCUUUAAUUCUGUAUCUGUAGACGGCUCAGUAUAGAUACCCUACGCUGUCCAGAAAGGUUUGGGGCAGAAAGGACUCCUCCUUUUUCCAUGCCCUAAACAGACCUGACAGGUGAGGUCUGUUCCUUUUAUAUAAGUGGACAAAUUUUGAGUUGCCACAGGAGGGGAAGUAGGGAGGGGGGAAAUACAGUUCUGCUCUGGUUGUUUCUGUUCCAAAUGAUUCCAUCCACCUUUCCCAAUCGGCCUUACUUCUCACUAAUUUGUAGGAAAAAGCAAGUUCGUCUGUUGUGCGAAUGACUGAAUGGGACAGAGUUGAUUUUUUUUUUUUUUUCCUUUGUGCUUAGUUAGGAAGGCAGUAGGAUGUGGCCUGCAUGUACUGUAUAUUACAGAUAUUUGUCAUGCUGGGAUUUCCAACUCGAAUCUGUGUGAAACUUUCAUUCCUUCAGAUUUGGCUUGACAAAGGCAGGAGGUACAAAAGAAGGGCUGGUAUUGUUCUCACACUGGUCUGCUGUCGCUCUCAGUUCUCGAUAGGUCAGAGCAGAGGUGGAAAAACAGCAUGUACGGAUUUUCAGUUACUUAAUCAAAACUCAAAUGUGAGUGUUUUUAUCUUUUUACCUUUCAUACACUAGCCUUGGCCUCUUUCCUCAGCCUUAAGAACCAUCUGCCAAAAAUUACUGAUCCUCGCAUGAUGGCAGCCAUAGUGCAUAGCUACUAAAAUCAGUGACCUUGAACAUAUCUUAGAUGGGGAGCCUCGGGAAAAGGUAGAGGAGUCACGUUACCAUUUACAUGUUUUAAAGAAAGAAGUGUGGGGAUUUUCACUGAAACGUCUAGGAAAUCUAGAAGUAGUCCUGAAGGACAGAAACUAAACUCUUACCAUAUGUUUGGUAAGACUCCAGACUCCAGCUAACAGUCCCUAUGGAAAGAUGGCAUCAAAAAAGAUAGAUCUAUAUAUAUAUAUAAAUAUAUAUUCUAUUACAUUUUCAGUGAGUAAUUUUGGAUUUUGCAAGGUGCAUUUUUACUAUUGUUACAUUAUGUGGAAAACUUAUGCUGAUUUAUUUAAGGGGGAAAAAGUGUCAACUCUUUGUUAUUUGAAAACAUGUUUAUUUUUCUUGUCUUUAUUUUAACCUUUGAUAGAACCAUUGCAAUAUGGGGGCCUUUUGGGAACGGACUGGUAUGUAAAAGAAAAUCCAUUAUCGAGCAGCAUUUUAUUUACCCCUCCCCUAUCCCUAGGCACUUAACCAAGACAAAAAGCCACAAUGAACAUCCCUUUUUCAAUGAAUUUUAUAAUCUGCAGCUCUAUUCCGAGCCCUUAGCACCCAUUCCGACCAUAGUAUAAUCAUAUCAAAGGGUGAGAAUCAUUUAGCAUGUUGUUGAAAGGUUUUUUUUCAGUUGUUCUUUUUAGAAAAAAAGAAAAACAAAAACAAAAACAAAAAAAAAAAAUCACACCAUUGCUCACAGAAUUGGCAUCUCAUUUUUGGGACCUCCCAUCUUUCUGUUUUGAAAAGUGUACAGUAGUGCAGUGUUCCUGAUGUAACUUUAUGGCUUACAAUGUUGACAUGUCUCAGGUUCAUGUGUUGCGAUUGGUGUUUUCCGUCUCAGGUAGAUUGCAAAGUGUAGGCCCCACACAUUGGAAAAAAUAAUAAUAAAACAAAGCAAAAACAGGAAAUUAUGGAUUUUAGUUGUAUAUUGGUUUAUGUAUUUUUUCUUAAGUAUACAGUGCACUGUUUGAAAUGUAUUGUUGAGUAUUACUUUGUACAGGUUGAUCACUUUUUUUAGAGUGAAGAAAGAACAAACUUGUUUUUUGUGUUUUUUAAAGGAAUAUAAAAUAAUGAAGGAUGUAUAAUUGAUGCCAAAUAAGCUUGUUCUUUAGUCACACCGACGUCUUAUUUUUCCCUUUAGGCCAGUUCUGUUUUUAAGGUGUACAUGGACAAUGUUACAGUGUAAGAAACUCCAUAUCCAUAUGUUCCCAUUCGCAUUUUGUAUUGGUUCAUGUAUACCAUUUUUACAAAAAAAAAAAGAAAAAAAAGAAGUACUAUAAAAUAUCUGUCUUCUUAAUAAAAAAAAAUUAAUGUUACAAAGUGAUCCUUUAAUCUCUUUAUGGACUUCUUAUGGACGCCUCCGAGUGAGAGAAGAGAUGGGCCUCUGGUCCCAGCUUCCUCCUUAGGACCAUGUACGGGGCCAGGAACGCUGGCAGUAGAUGCUAGGACAUGCUGCCGGCUGGGUUGCUGGGGGCCGCGCUCUCUCUCCUUCUCCGCUCAUCCUUCCUGUCCUUGUUCUCUUCCCCACUCUCAGUGGACAGGUGAGCCAAGUGCUGUGCCGUGGCUGAGUCUGGGCUCCCACGUGGACUCAGCGAUUUGUGCAGGUGUGCGAGCUGUCGUGGCGGGCCCGCCGGAACAGGCCGCUCCCGUAGAUGUGUCUUCCGCACUCAUCCCCUCUCUCACCGCCCCCCCACCCUCACCAACUUCCCUGUGUUGGCUGCUCCACCUGUCUCUUACUUUGGGAGUUUGUGUCUUAACAAUUCAUUCUGCCUUCUUCCUUGAAAGUUCUCUCUCCUUUCAUAAAAAGAAGACGUGAGCUGUGGAGGACUGGCUUGGCUGCCUGCAGAAGAUUGUUCUCACUUGCUGUUUAGGUUGCUGAGACUUCCAGGCCUGGGUAGACAGCAGGAUUUGCUCUGUUGUCAUCGUCCUUGCCUUGCAGGCUGAAGUGAGCAAUGACUACACUUCAUGGUGGCCGAUCUUAUAAAUGUGCAGAUAACGUCUGGCCAGGCCCAAAGUGCCCUUUUCCCACCAUCCCCUCAGCUGUGGUUGAUGAGUUCCCCUUUUCUCCCUUGGCCACGUCAUGGGGAAAGUUCCAUAGGAAAAGCAAAGGUAAGCUCCAGAAAGACUGAAGGCUGUGCAUCUCCCCUUGAGCCACUUCCAUCCUGGCCUGGUCUCUUACCUGUCUCUGUUAAAAAAAAAAAAAAAAAAAAAAAAAAAAAAAAAUCAGAUAUGCAGUUAUUGAGCACCUGCUGUAUGUCCAGCAUGGUGAGGGAUGCAGAGAAGUAUAAGGCGGUCUCUGGAGGCCAAGUAGAGCAUCAGUUACAUCACCUGAAAACUUGAAGUGACCCUGAGCCAUGGGUGCCCCACUGAACACAGAGAAGCCCAGAGAGUGCUAUGAGAAUUUUCUGGAGAAGGGUAAUCAGUGAAGGCUGGUGAGUCCCUAGACAGCUUCACAAAGAGCUGGGACCCCAGCUGGAUCUUAAAGGAUGGUUUCGUGGAGAAGGAAUGUGAGUCAAAAGUACAGAGGGCAACAAGCCCAGCCAGCCUGCUGAUUUGUAUGGGGAGAAGAAAGCAAUUCCGUGUGCAGGGUGGGAUGGGUCUUGUGGCUGUACUGAAAAGUCCGGGCAGAGGACUCGAUACUUCAGUGACCUCUCCCAGCCUCUGCCAGAGGGCAAGGAGCAGUAGGGAGUACUCAUUCAUUGCAUCUCUAUAAAAAGACCCAGAGAGAUAGAAUAAGGAUCAAAAGCACACACUAGAGAGAGGCUGCCUGCAUUCAGAUCCCUGUCCCACCAUGUAGCAGUGAAACCUCGGGUGAGUAGCCCAGCCUACCUGGCUUCAGUCUCUUGCUCUGCAAGGUGGACAUCACCAUAGCCUCGAAGGUUGUUAGGAAAGAUCAGUGAGAUAUGCAGUCAGCGCUCAGCCAAAAAGGUGCCAGACACACACUACUUGUUCAUUACAUGUCAGUCACAGGAUAGAGGCAAAUGGUGACUAAAACGAUAGAAGGUUACCCAGGGCUACGAAGAAGCGGUCACUACUCAGAGGGAGCUCUGAGGGCUCCUCUGCAUAUAGACACAUCAUGCCCUUGCAAACCACGACUUAGAAGGUUUAAUGACCCUUUUCUCUUCACCAUUCAUUAGCAGACUUAUUCCAAGCCACGUGGCAUGCAGUAUGUUUAGUCUCCCCACCCCUCUCCCUCUUGUCUGCAGCAUGAGGCUCCAGCUUUAGCUGUACCCUACAGAAAAAAGUCCCAGAAGUUCCUUGAGCUGAGGCAGACAGGAGGUGGUGACUGCUGUACAUUUGCCUUUUGAGCUCCACAGGGUAUGCAAAUGAGAAGGUGCUAGAAGCCGUCCCCGCUCAAAGGAUCUUGAUAAGUUGCCCACUCCUUCAUUUGAGAAGAGUGCGUACGAGAGUGAAAAUGGCCCUCGUUUCCCCCAGAGAGUUUUCACAAAUGUUUUGGCCUGGCAUUCUCCAAAUACAUCAACUGGAACCCUGAGGUGAUAUGCGGGUGUUAAUUGGUGCAAUCUUUCACUGUCCUCUGUCUACCUGAAAUGUAAUUCUUUUACCGCUGUGGACUUGCUCCAUGGAGAAAUGCUCCUUUGAUUCUGUCAUCAAGAACCUCAAAGAAACCAUGUGGCCACUGUGUUACAGGUAGAAAGACCCUGCUUAAGUGAAGGUAUUUUUGUUUUAUUAUAAAAUCAUGCCCAAGAUUAAUACACCUUUUUGCCAGGAUCCCAAAUACGCAGCCCUUUGUCAUGAAGAACUGGCAGCCACAUUCCUUCAGGGUGAAAUUUGUAUUCACAGCCAUACAUGUAUAGUUUUUGAAGCGCUGGCCCCCCGUACAGGAGAAGAAAGAAGGGACUCUUGGCUCAUCCAUGACCUUGUAGGUCAAUACCAUAUUAAAGUUCCUGUCAGGCACGCAGUAGUCACCCAGCAAGUAUCAGCUGAUUAAAGGGAGAAGAGUCGAGCACCUGGCUGACUGAGCCUUACGUUACACUUAAUCUGAAUGGGCCACCGAUGCUGUAUUUCAAACCUUGAUGUUUGCAUGUCCAUCCUUACUACAGGUGGCUUUCAGGUUGGCCGUGAAGGGACAAGCCAGCCAGUCCUGAGUUUAGAGCGAUUGGCCCUAUCAUUCUCAAGGACCCACUGGAAUAGUAUCAGGGAAUAUCAUUUUGGGUAAUGGCCAAGCAAAGCCUUAGUAUUGCUAUCAUAUAUUGUGAGGGGCCUUCAGAAUGCAAUAUGGCCUCUUUUAAAAAUGCAAACUAUAGUCCUUGCCUUAUCUGUGUUUAUCUCAAAAUGUUGAAAUGUGCCUCUAAUAGGAACUGCAGGAUUCAGUCCCCCCCCACCACCCCCCACCCAACACUCACAUCAUUACACAUGAGCAUCCCUGAACUGAGACCUGAAAGCAAGAAUCUUCUCUGUUUUCAGGUGUUCCAAACCUCAGCUUCCAGCCUCUUCAGUACACAGGAAACUUUGUUUCAUUUUUAUGUUUUUAUUUAUUUUUUUCAUUCCCAAAAAACAUAAAAUGUCUACUGCCCCUGGUGGUCAGUGCUGGGAAAUACAACUCGAGCCUUGCCUAUUGAAAUGCAGAAUGUAUUCCAACAAGGAACCUGACAUUGUCUACUGCUUUUUCUCUCACACACAUGCACACCUACCUGCGCCUCCCAUUUUACUCCCUCCUAAUCCUUCGAAGUGUUGAUCUGGGGAAGGUGAGAACCACUACUGAGGGGCAAAUCAACCGGUUCUCUGGGCCCGGGACUUCAGCUGCCCUCCAGACGUGCACAGGCUCACAGUCAUAUUUCAGACGUGACCGCCUCAAAUCUUCCUUAAGUGCUAUCUUCUCAGGUUAAUUAAUCACCAGGCUUAAACUUGCUGUUACCAGCAGGAAGUCCAUCCUGAAGUCAGCAAUGUUACGAUUGCAUCUUCUAAUACUGUUUAUCCUGCAUUAGUGUUUACUUAGGGGGAAAAUUGAUCCGUAAUUGAUAUUUCAGUCUUCCAGAGCUGGUGUUGGAAGAGCCUAAUGCAGGCCUUUAAUAGCAAGCAAAUAUUUAAAUCCCUUAAUGGUUGCUGAAUAUUGAAAUGUGUGACUUUAUUACUCUUUUUGGUUUGUUUUCUCUGUAGUUGUGUAUUUCAUCGUUUAAACCUGCAAUGGAUGCUGGCAAGUGCAAGUCUAGCUAAUCCACAAAAGCUGUUUGCCCAGACACAGCAGACCUGAUUAAAAAGUAUUGCUAUGGAAGGGAAUCUUCUGCACUAAUCAGUCUCUGUUAGCUAGUGACGAAAUUACUAUCCAUCUCUCUCUCUUUCUCUUUCUCUCCCUCUCUCUAGGCCUGUUUUCUCUAACCUCCUCUCCCAGAAUAAAGUGAUGAGGGCAGCUAUAGUGUUGCAAUUAGGAACAUGAAUCUUUUAUCGUUUGGACAAGGAAGGGAAAAUGCCAUUACUGUCAACUGAAAUGUCCUACUUGGGUUUUUUGCUCCUACUUCCCUGCCAAAGCCCAUUGCUGCUGCUGAAAUUGUAUAACAUUCACAGCUGUUCUUGAUGGCUUGAUUCUUAACACAGCCAGAAAUGUAGCCCGGGAGAUGCUUAAGACAGUUUAUGGAAAAUAAUAGAUUUCCUUGCAGAGACACCAAUGCAUCGAGAAGGGCCUUGAGUCACGUUAGCCCCAGCCAAGAUCACCAAUUUUCUCUCUAUCUGGCUUCAGUUACAAAGGCUAUGCCUU